CUGGCGAGCCGGCGCCGGCCGAGCUGCGGGAGCCGCGGAGAGCACCAGCUGACGCCGCGGGAGCUGCUCCGGCCGCACCAUGCGGGAGCUGGCCAUUGAGAUCGGGGUGCGAGCCCUGCUCUUCGGAGUCUUCGUGUGCCUCUGAAGAUGACGUCUCAUUUACUGCAUGAAUAAGGAGCGGUUCAGGCAGCUGUCAUAUAUCAAAUCCAAUUCUCAUUUUACAGAGUUUUUGGAUCCGUUCCAGAGAGUCAUCCAGCCAGAAGAGAUCUGGCUCUAUAAAAAUCCUUUGGUGCAAUCAGAUAACAUACCUACCCGCCUCAUGUUUGCAAUUUCUUUCCUCACACCCCUGGCUGUUAUUUGUGUGGUGAAAAUUAUCCGGCGAACAGACAAGACUGAAAUUAAGGAAGCCUUCUUAGCGGUGUCCUUGGCUCUUGCUUUGAAUGGAGUCUGCACAAACACUAUUAAAUUAAUAGUGGGAAGACCUCGCCCCGAUUUCUUUUACCGCUGCUUUCCAGAUGGAGUGAUGAACUCGGAAAUGCAUUGCACAGGUGACCCCGAUCUGGUGUCCGAGGGCCGCAAAAGCUUCCCCAGCAUCCAUUCCUCCUUUGCCUUUUCGGGCCUUGGCUUCACGACGUUCUACUUGGCGGGCAAGCUGCACUGCUUCACCGAGAGUGGGCGGGGAAAGAGCUGGCGGCUCUGUGCUGCCAUCCUGCCCUUGUACUGCGCCAUGAUGAUUGCCCUGUCCCGCAUGUGCGACUACAAGCAUCACUGGCAAGAUUCCUUUGUGGGUGGAGUCAUCGGCCUCAUUUUUGCAUACAUUUGCUACAGACAGCACUAUCCUCCUCUGGCCAACACAGCUUGCCAUAAACCCUACGUUAGUCUGCGAGUCCCAGCCUCACUGAAGAAAGAGGAGAGGCCCACAGCUGACAGCGCACCCAGCUUGCCUCUGGAGGGGAUCACCGAAGGCCCGGUAUGACCAGUGUCCUGGGAGGAUGGACACUAAGCCCUGGGCACAUCUGCCACCCUGACAUCAUAACACAAUAGAAAUGGUUUUCUGUAGUGUAUUUUUCAUCAGUUGUUUCUCAAAGUCAUCGUACUUCUGCUUCUGUUUCACUGAUGGUGUUCCUGCUACUUUAAAUGUCUACUUCCAACAUCCUUGAAUUUGCAAGUGAAGGACAACAAUCUCUGAGAGACGUGUGGAAGAGGCUGUGAAGGUGGGGUUUGGGGAGCUUGGCCGAUUCGUCUAUCUGAAAUGUUUGCUGUAACAGCCACCUUCCUAUGUUUUCAUGGUUGUAAAACAUAAUAAAACCUCCCACGUGGAAGACUUGGUGUUGGCCACCCAGCGCAACAAGUCAUUUGGAGAUGCAGCAGGUUUCUCAGAGACCCAAAGCCAGCUCUGUCUGUAGGUCAUUCCAGGUGCUGAGCUUGGAAGCAAAGGCUCAGAACCUUUCUGAGCCAUCAGCUUCUCAUAGCCCACGUCUCUAAAAUAGAUUUGAAACUUGGAGUGACAGCUUGAGCAUUUCCAGGGCUUUUGAAUCAUUGAAUCUGGAAGCAAAUAAAAUUAAUAACUUCAUGCACAGACUUCCACCAAACACAAUGAGCAUGAAGAUGCAUGAGUGCAUGUGUGGGGGAUGAGGUCACAGCAGUUGCCUGAGGGUUCAUGGGCACAAUAUCCUUCCCAUCUUCCAGUCUAAGUUUAUGGAGCCACUUCUGUAGCUCUGCCUCAUACAGUGAAUUUUUGGGGCACGGGGGCUUUACUUGGCUCUUCUGCAAGAAGUGAUGUGACCGAUCUCACAGAUCAGAAACCGCAUGCCUGGGGCUCAUCUCAAGGGAGUGGCUGAGUGGCCAUUGGGGAUAAGAAGCAACUUCAGGCUGAGAAUUUUUCCCCUUUAGGAUCUGAGUUUUGCAGAGCUCUGCUCUAAGGAUUCUCCAAGUGGUGGUGUGUUCCUGUUCCUAUCUAGCUGGCAAUAUUUCAGCAUGAUAGGACUCUGGUAGAAGGUACAAGAACAGAAUCAGGAAUGUGCUGUGUCUCUCGCUCAGCUCUUUGCAUUGUUGAAUACAGCCAGUCAAUAUGAACCUUUUUCAGUCUGAGUAUAGAGCACGCUGCUCCUUGGCCAGCUAGUUUUUUCAAGGCAAGGAGCAUCCCCUUCAUCCAAUUCUGAUUGGAUGUACCAUGUGGUUGUUCAGAUUCCUGGGCCUGGGUGCUACGAGGUGAUGCAUCUUUGCUAUCCAGAGUGUCACUUUUUUUUUUUUUUUUUUGAGAUGGAGUCUCGCUGUGUCGAGACUGCACUGGAGUGCAGUGGCGUGAUCUUGGCUCACUGCAACCUUUGCCUCUGGGUUCAAGCUAUUCUCGUGCCUCAGCCUCCCAAGUAGCUAGGACUACAGGUGCCCGCCACCACACCUGGCUAAUUUUUGUAUUUUUAGUAGACACGGGGUUUCACCACGUUGGCCAGGCUGGUCUCGGACUCCUAGCCUCAAGUGAUCUGCCCACCUCGGCCUCCCAAAGUGCUGGGAUUAUAAGCGUGAGCCACUGCACCUGGCCAAGAGUGUUGCUUUUGGGCAGUUAGCAUAACAGACUGCAUUUUGAGAGACUCAGGUGGCUGCCUAAAUGGUCAGCUUAUCAGCCCUGGGCUGCGUGUGCAAGUUAGAAGCAUCAGAAUAUCUUUGAUCAGCCAUUUCUGUUAAGCUCCAUGGGCUUAAGCUUGGAGUGCAUGUACCACUGACUAUGCUCCAUGAGCCCCAGUGCAGCCCUCUCCAGCCCUGGUCCUUCCAAACUGGCUUUGGCACGGUCAUGUGAUUGUCCCCUGGAUGGAGUGGGAGAGGGGGAGGCUUGAAUUGACUUUCAUCCAAAGUCAAGCCAUUGAUUUUUUAAAAAUUAUAGCAGUUACAUUGGCAAGCAACUUUGAAGAUGAAUGUGAGAUAUUUUAAGAGAUAAAUCAUAGCAAUUGAAAAGACAUAAUUUUAAAUUCUGAGCUAAAAUUCAUUUAAAAUUAGAAAAUUAAACAAUACUCUAAUUUAACUAAAAACUCUAUAAUUUUCAAAAAUAAAGCCCAAAAUAGAAAUGUAGGAAAAAGAUCCUUUGCUACUGUUAAAAAAAAAAACCCCAUCCUGAUGUGGCCCACAUUCUUAUUUGAUUCUAGUUUUAUCUGAGCAAGAGGAAAGGAAAAGGGUUGUACUUCAGUUAAUAAAGACUUAAAAUUCUGGACCAUCAAGUGUAAAUUUAAUAUAAAUAAUUUUAUUUAAAGAUAAAUGGCCAGGAAGUACUCUGCAAAGUAACAACAGAGUAUUACUAAUGCUGAUAAUUACAUGGAAAAUCCUAAUACUGGCCAUGUAAAAGCUUUGAUUAAAAUAUAAUUCAAAUUACAGAUGAUGUAAUAACAUGAAGCUGGUGGUAGGAUCCUCAGGAGCCAUAAUGAACAGUGUAAGCCAGUUCACAAAAGGCAGGCAUUUUUACAGAUCCUUAUGUUUCAAUUUCAUGCUCUAUUCACGUGAAGUAAAUAUAACAUCACAGUGUACCAAUUAAAUGGCCAUAAUGAGAA